AUAGACAGGCCAGCACAGCCAGCCUUGCAGCCUGAGAUAAGGCCUUUGGCGGGUGUCUCCCCUAUCGCUCCCUCAAGCCCUCAAGUAGGUGUUGGAGAGAGGGGUGAUGCCUGGUGCUGGUGGAACCCCUGCACAGAGACGGACACAGGAUGAGCUCUAAGUACCCGCGGUCUGUCCGGCGCUGCCUGCCCCUCUGCGCCCUAACACUGGAAGCAGCUCUCAUUCUCCUCUUCUAUUUUUUUACCCACUAUGACGCUUCCUUAGAGGAUCAAAAGGGGCUCGUGGCAUCCUAUCAAGUCGGCCAAGAUCUGACCGUGAUGGCGGCCCUUGGCUUGGGCUUCCUCACCUCAAAUUUCCGGAGACACAGCUGGAGCAGUGUGGCCUUCAACCUCUUCAUGCUGGCGCUUGGUGUGCAGUGGGCAAUCCUGCUGGACGGCUUCCUGAGCCAGUUCCCUCCUGGGAAGGUGGUCAUCACACUGUUCAGUAUUCGGCUGGCCACCAUGAGUGCUAUGUCGGUGCUGAUCUCAGCGGGUGCUGUCUUGGGGAAGGUCAACUUGGCGCAGUUGGUGGUGAUGGUGCUGGUGGAGGUGACAGCUUUAGGCACCCUGAGGAUGGUCAUCAGUAAUAUCUUCAACACAGACUACCACAUGAACCUGAGGCACUUCUACGUGUUCGCAGCCUAUUUUGGGCUGACUGUGGCCUGGUGCCUGCCAAAGCCUCUACCCAAGGGAACGGAGGAUAAUGAUCAGAGAGCAACGAUACCCAGUUUGUCUGCCAUGCUGGGCGCCCUCUUCUUGUGGAUGUUCUGGCCAAGUGUCAACUCUGCUCUGCUGAGAAGUCCAAUCCAAAGGAAGAAUGCCAUGUUCAACACCUACUAUGCUCUAGCAGUCAGUGUGGUGACAGCCAUCUCAGGGUCAUCCUUGGCUCACCCCCAAAGGAAGAUCAGCAUGACUUAUGUGCACAGUGCGGUGUUGGCAGGAGGCGUGGCUGUGGGUACCUCGUGUCACCUGAUCCCUUCUCCGUGGCUUGCCAUGGUGCUGGGUCUUGUGGCUGGGCUGAUCUCCAUCGGGGGAGCCAAGUGCCUGCCGGUGUGUUGUAACCGAGUGCUGGGGAUUCACCACAUCUCCGUCAUGCACUCCAUCUUCAGCUUGCUGGGUCUGCUUGGAGAGAUCACCUACAUUGUGCUGCUGGUGCUUCAUACUGUCUGGAACGGCAAUGGCAUGUCACCCGGCUGGAACCUGGCUGUAAAAAUGGCUGAAGCAGGUGAUGAGGAGCUGAUGUGUUUGGACGUGUCUCAGAGAAAUCAUGGAGGCGCUGGGGUUCCUUCCGGUUCUUGGAUGCCUUCUACAGAGACAACCAUAGCCCCAAAUUAUAGGGAUCACAUAUCAGUGGGUGAGACAUCCUUGCUUGGGAUGAGGAGGGGAUGAGCUGUGUGAAGCAAGGUGCCUCUGUAAUGGGUUCCAGUGAUGUGUCUGCCACUGUCUUAAUAACUGUGCAAUUCUAAGCAGAACCUUUCCUGUCUCUGGGCCUGAGAGUUCCCCUCUGUAAGAUGAGGACUUGACCUAGCAAGGUCCUACUCAGAUGCCUGUAGAGAACAGGCAGGGGAAGUUAGAAAAAAAAAAAGCCAGUGAAGGAAGGGAGCUCUUCAGCUUGCACCCACCAUCACAGUGCAGGGACCCAGGCUCAGUGUUGCCAGAUCCAAUGACUUCUCAAGAGCUCAAAAUCUAGAGUUUUGCAUGUGCUCUCCCAAGUACUGGCAGAAAAUUCAAGAUUGUUAGUAACACUGUGUGGCUAAAUUCUGCUUGUGGGCUGCCUAGAUUCCCAAUUCUGUGAUUCUGUGGUUCUCUGGAAGCAUUGGUUCUCCACAGCACCUGCAUCACUUGGAAACUUGUUAGAAAUGCAAGCCCUACCUACGGCCCCACCCCAGACCUACCCAGUUAGAAAUCUGGGGGUGGGACCUAUCAGUCCAUGUUUGAACAAGCCCCACAAGUGUUCUCUUGCAAGCUCAAGUUUUAGAACCACUGACCUAUAGCCAAAAAAGAAAAAGCCAAUCAGUGGUUUGCUGGUAGAGGAUUAACUUAACAACUGGCUUUCCAUGAAAAUAAAGCCUUGAUUGGUAGCACUUGCAAUUUCUAUGGUACAAACGCUUCCCACAUGACUGAGUUCAAGCUAUCAAGGAGACGUCACUGCACAUGGACUUGGGAAGAGAUGAGAACAAUCAGCCCACUGAGCCUAUGGGAACUGGCUCCAGCACAUCCCUGCAAGUCAACUCUCAUCAGGGUGAGUGAGUUGAGGACCAAGAAGCAGUUAUCCUCUUGCCUUUGCAGGACCCAGGCAAAGGGAAGGGCAUAGUGACAGUGAUGAUCUCUCUUCCGGAAGUCUUUGGUUUGCUGAGAGUAAAAGGCGUGGGCUUCACCAGUGGUGAAGCCAGUCAUGCAGCCUUAGUCCUGGUACUCAAACUCCCUAAAUCUCAGUUUUCUAUCUGUAAAAUGGGAAAAUAAGUCCUAUGUCACAGGGUUGCUGUGCAGAUUUAGCAAUAGAACAUAGCCCCGUUCUUUAUGAUGACUGAUGCUGCAUCAGUAUGGGGACAUCUCUAUGUAAUGGAAAGAUGGAGAGAGGAUUAAGUGCAAAGUCACAGCACUUAAUGGGAACUGUGGAUUAGCUACUUGGUGGCAUUGGGCAAGUCAGUUGACUUUGCAUUAAUUCCACAAACAAUAUUUCCCAAUUUCCUAUUCAGAUGAGCAUAUGUGACUGAGUCAGAUGCUGUGAUCAGAGCCAGGAUGGAGCAUUUCCCACAAACUGUGGGAUUUUUAAGUGAUGGGAAGGCACACUGAAAUGGCAUUGAAUCAUGCAGUUGCAGAUACUCUUUUUCAAUUCUCAGUCCUUUGAUUACAUCAGGGAGAAAAGAAAGUCCCCACUUGGGCUGAGAAUCUCUGCACCCUUCUAGCUCUUGUUAACCACUCUUUUGAAUAGCAGAGAAAACCUCAGACUGCCAUAUCUGGGAGAGAUUUUAGCAACAUUUUGUUUUCAUUGUAUCUCUUUUUACAGCUACCUCCCAUUUCCCUUCUAUUUCAAGCUAGUAACACAGUUUUCUUUUAAAUUCAUUUAUUUAAAUGUAAAAAUAAGUCUAUUUGGAGAAAAAAAAUUUUUAAUAGCAUCUCUGGAAUGCCAGUAUGGCUAAAUUCAUGAAUGUUGUCCUCAAAUGCUGAAAUCUGGGAAGCAUCUGGCCAAGCUUUGUGGACAGGCCUUCCUAGUUUGAAUCCCAAGAGCCACUCAUUCCGAGCCACAAAACAUUGGAAUUCUUGGUUCACUUCCCUAACCUGAACUUGUCCUCUGUGAAAUAGGGACAUUAAUAGCUCACUCACAGGGCUGCUGUGAGGACAUGUGUUGAGCUGAGGGUCUGGCCAGGGGAGACCCUGUGCAGGGAGACUGUUAUCAUGGUGAUGGAUUUCUGCUUCAUUCAUUUCUUUUUCCAGACAGCAUCAUAUAGAAUGAGUUGUGGGGUGGCAGUCAGCAGGUUUGGGUUUAUCCUCUAUUCUGCCACUUAUUACUUAAAAAAAAAAACCCAACUUAUAUAGUAUAAGCUAUAUCCAGAAAAGUGCAAAUAUCAUACAAGUACCAUUUGAUGAAUCUUCUGAUAUCCCCACAUAACCAACACCCAGAACCUCUUCUUGUCUCAUUCCAGGAUAACCACUAACCUGACUUCUAACAGCAUCAGUCAGUUUUGUCUGUUUUUGUACAUUAUAUAUGUGAUGGUUUGAAUGUGUCCCCCAAAUUUCAUGUGCUAGAAACUUAAUCCUUCAAUUCAUAUGUUGAUGCUAUUUGGAGGAAGGGCCUUUGGGAAGUAAUUAGGAUUAGAUAAGGUCAUGGGGUGAGGUAUGAUGGCACUGGUGACUUAUAAGAAGAGAAAGAGAAAUCUGAGCUGGCAUGCUCUUGCCCUCUCACCGUGUGAUGACUUCUCCAUGUCAUGAUGCAGCAAGAAGGCCCUCACCAGAUGGUGGCACCAUGCUUUUGGACUUCCCAGCCUCUAGAACUGUGAGCUAAAUCAAUUUAUUUUCUUUAUAAUCACCCAGUUUGAUAUUUUGUCAUAGCAACAGAAUAUGGACAAAGAAAGAAAAUUAAUGCAAGAAGUAGAGUUUUUACUGUAACAGAUUCCUGAAAAUGUGGAAGUGGCUUUGGAACUGGGUGAUGGGAAUAGGUUGGAAGAGUUUUGAGGAGCAGGCUAGAAAAAGCCUGUAUUGUCAAGAAUGGAGCAUUAGGCCAGGCACGGUGGCUCAGACUUAUAAUCCCAGCACUUUGGGAGGCCAAAGCAGGUGGAUCACCUGAGGUCAGGAGUUCGAGACCAGCCUGGCUAACAUGGUGAAACGCUGUUUCUACCAAAAAUACAAAAAAUUAGCUGGGCACUCUGGCGCACACCUGUAAUCCCAGCUACUCAGGAGGCUGAAGCAGGAGAAUCACUUGAACCCAGGAGGCAGAGGUUGCAGUGAGCUGAGAUCGUGCUAUUGCACUCCAGCUUGGGCAACAAGAGCAAAACUCCAACUCAAAAAAAAAAAAAAAAGAAAAAGAAAAAGAAUGGAGCAUUAAAGACAGUUCUACAGUUCUGGUGAGGGCUUAAAAGAAGACCCCAGAACUAGGGAAAGUCUGGAACUUCUUAAUGGUUACUGAAGUCGUUGAGAUCAGAAUGCUGAUAGAAAUGUGGCUGGUGAAGGCCAUUCUGAUGAGGUCUCAGAUGGAACUGAAGAACCACGUGUUGGAAACUGGAGCAAAGGUCAUCCUUUUUAUAAAGAAGCAAAGAUCUUAGCUGAACUUUGUCUGUGCCAGAGUCAUUUAUGGAAAGCAGAAAAUCCGUAGGUCACCCAUGUUGUAGAGAAUGAAAGAACAUUUUCAGCUGAGAAAACUGAGAGUGUGACCAAGCUACCGAUUGAUAAGAAAACUAGUACACAUAAAUUAGCCAGGCGUGGUGGUGGGCGCCUGUAGUCCCAGCUACAUGGGAGGCUGAGGCAGGAGAAUGGCAUGAACCCGGGAGGCAGAGCUUGCAGUGAGCCGAGAUCGCGCCACUGCACUCCAGCCUGGGCGACAAAGCGAGACUCCAUCUCAAAAAAAAAAAAAAAAAAAAGGAAGAAAGAAAAUUAGUACACAUAGAACAAAGCCAGAGGCUGUUCAUCAGGACAAGGGAGAAAAACUCCAAAGCCAUUUCAGAGAUCUUCAAGACUGCCCCUCCCAUUACUGGCCCAGAGCUCUAAGAGGGCAGAAUGGUUUGGAAUGACCAGCUGCUGCCCAGGGCUGCCUUGGGUCUCUGCUCCCCACAUUUCUGGUGCAGCAUUCCUCAGCCAUCCCAGCUGUGGUUCAAGUGGCCACAGGUGUGAUGUGGAAGGUAAAAGUCAUAAACCUUGGCAGCAUACACAUGGCACUAAUUUUGCAGGUGUGCAGAAUGCAAAAGCUGAGGGGGCAUGCCUUCUCCCACCUACAUUUCAAAGGGUGCUGUGAACGGCCACCCCAGAGAGCCCCUAGUAGAGCAAGGUCUAGUGGAGCUACAAGGGUGGGGCCACCGCCAAGACCCCAGAAUGGUAGAGCUAUCAUAGUGCAAUGCCAGCUUGGGAGAACUGCAGGCAUGAGACUCCAACCUGUGCGAAGUGCAACAUGGGCAGAACCCAGCAAAACCACAGGGGCAGAGCUCCCCGAAGCUUCGGGGGUCCAAAUUCCAUAGUGUGUCCAGGAGGUGGCACACAGAGUAAAAGAUCAUUCUGAAGGUUUAAGGUUUAAUGUUGUUUUCUAUGUUGGGUUUUGUACUUUCCUGGAACCAGUUACCCUUUUUCCCUUGCCUCUUUUUCCUUUUAGAAUGGGAAUGUCUGUCCUAUGCCUGUUCCACUGUUGUAUUUUGGAAGUCAAUAACUUGUUUUGACUUUACAGGCUUACAGCCAGAGGGAAUCUCCCAUAGAAUGAAUUGUACCUUAAGUCUCACCCACAUCUGAUUUAGAUGAGACCAUGGACUUUGGAAUUUUGAGUUGGUGCUGGAACAAGUUAAGACUUUGGGGGUUGUCUAAGUGUGGUGUUUCAUGCCUGUAAUCCCAGUGAU